GCUAAAGGCCUGAGGCCACUGCAGCUGCCGCAGCUCUCCCUCUGAGGUCUUGCGCCCGAGGUAGGGGCGGCUUUUAUUUUUUUUUUUAAUCCUUAAAGGCGGAGACGGCGGCGGUGGCGACUUUACGUUGACGUCUUUGAAAACCUGCUUACCUUUUUCAGGGCUCUCCAGCCCUCGCCUCCAGAUGUGAAUUGGACUUAGGAUAGUUUUUUCAGGGCAGUAGGAAUUGCUUGUGGAUCCAGUUUGUACUCUUAUGUGCUACUUAUUUCGUGUGCGUAUUAUUGUUUAUGCCCUCUUCUUUCUCCCCUUAAAAAGAAACUACUUUUUUAUUUACCUUGAAUAUAUUUUUGAGCUUUCUUUUCUUUUUUCUUUUUUUUUUUUUUUGAGACAGAGUCUCGCCCUGUCGCCCGCGCUGGAGUGCAGUGGCGUGAUCUCGGCUCAACUGCAACCUCUGACUCCCGGGUUCAAGUAUUUUUCCUGUCUCAGUCUCCCACGUUGCUGGGAUUACAGGCGUGCGCCACCACGCCCGGCUAGUUUUUGUAUUUUUAGUAGAGAGAGGGUUUCACCAUGUUGGCCAGGCUGGUCUUGAACUCCUGACCUCAAGUGAUCCGUCUGCCUCGGCCUCCUAAAGUGCUAGGAUUACAAGUGUGAGCCACCGCGCUUGGCCUUGAGCUACUUUUUAAAAGUUAAGUUCACUCGCAAAGGAUGUGUGCCAUUCACCAUUGACAAAAAUCUUAAGACCAUUCAGUAUUACCUGUUGGGAUGGUUUUUGUUGUUGUUGUUGUCUUGUUUUUGCCUAUUAGAAGUUGAUCUAUACUGCUAGUAUAAAUAACAUCUGCUCUGUGCUAAUGGACUGGGAAAAGUACAAAGCUAAAAAAGUUAUUGGCUCAAUAACUUGAGCCAAUAACAUGUCUAAUCACUGUGCUGUGAAAUAAAAGACGUUAAGAAGAUAUUUCCUGCAAUCAAGGGUGGGAAGGUCAAGGACAGCAGCAAAUUUGUUUUAAAACAAAUUCCACACAGCACCUGUGUGAGCACUGGGGAAGCAGCGCCUAACAUAACUGCCCAGAAACUAACUGCAGGUCAUUCCUAUAGCCUUGCUGGAGCAAGGGGCCUGGAGAGAGGUGGGGGAGAUUAACCCAUCCUGGGAUGAGUCAUGCAGGGCCCACCGAGCCCUAUCAUGUGGGAUUGUGCUCAAAGGGAGAGCAUAAGGUUUCCUGUUAGGUGGUAAGAUUCAUUCCGCUGUCACUGCUGAACACCUACUGUGCACCAGGCUCCGAGGUCAGUUCUUGAGAUAUCACCAUGAACAAGACAGGCAGGAGUUGUGACUAUUCUGUCUUUGACACGCAGUCAUAAGGGAGAUGGGGACAGGUGUUGCUGUAGAAGCCGGAAGGAGAGGCACUGAACUUGGACAUGGGGGAGUUAGGGAGCAAGACCGGUGCUAGGGCAUAACAACAUGUCAGAGUUUUCAGAGGUGAAAGUAAGGCGGAGUCCUCCAGUAUGGCUGCAGAGUGUGUUAGUGGGAGGGUGAGAACAUAGGCCAAAACGGUUAGCAGGAGCCCUGUGAUACAUGAAAGGCCCUGCAACCAGCAGUUUGGACUUUAUCCUGAGAGGAAUAUGAACCAAUUAAAGGGUAUUGGUUUGGUUGGGUUUUUUAAAAUUAUAAUUCAAUUAGUAUUAAUGACAAAUUUGUGGGAUACUCUGUAGCUCCUAAUACAUUUGUCAUUACUUGUAUUUUUAUUCCAUCUUUUUUUUUGGUCUUGUUUUUAAGCUAGUAACUUCAAAUUUCACAAAACAUUAUCUUUCAUUGAAGGGUUUUAUUUCUGAAAGCAGCAUGAUCAAAUUUGCAGUUUUAAAAGAUGACUCAGGCGGGGCAUGGUGGCCCACACCUAUAAUGCUAACACUUUGGGAGGCAGAGGUGAGCAGAUUGCUUGAGUCCAGGAGUUUGAGACCAGCCUGUGCAACAUAGCGAAACCCCGUCUCUACAAAAAAAUUAGCUGGGCACGGUGACACACACCUGUGGUCCCAGCUACUCGUGAGGCUGAGGUGGGAGGAUCACCUGAGCCUGAGAGGUCAUGGUUGGCAGUGAGCCAUGAUUGUGCCACUACACUCCAGCCUAGGCAUCAGAGCAAGACCUUGUCUCUAAAUAAAUAAUAAAACAGAAGAUGACUAUGGCUUCAGGGUAAAGAGUGGAUUAGAGGGGUCAUAUAGAUGACAAAUGGGUAAAAAAUUGGUGGCCGUCACCAAGGCAAGAGAUAACAGGGUUCUCAGCUGGAAUGGAUUGGUGGAUUUGAGAGCUGUUUUGGAGAUAGAGUGAACAAGUGUGGAGAGGCCAAGUCCAAGGAUGGUGCUCAGGUUUCUGGCUGGGGUGCUAGAGAAAUGGCAUGGCAUUCACUGGGAUGGGGCACCUUGGAGGAGGAGCUGGUCGGAGGUGUGGGAGAAAGGUAAGUUCAGGUUUGGAAACAUCAUCUGAGGUGGCCAUCUGAGUACGUGGCUGUGUGAGACUGAGCUCCAGCGAGAGGCUGAGAGUGUGGAGGGGAGGGUGGAAAUGGAACCCUUGGAAGUGGAUGAAGAGCCAUGGGAGUAUGGUUCAUUUAAGGGAGAGGCCAGAGAAGUGGGAGGAAACCCAGGACAGUAUUAAUCUCUGAAGCCAAAGGAAGAGAGCAUUUCAAGGAGGGAGUGGUGGUGAAUAGUGGAAUGCACUGAGUGGCCUAAGUAUCCUGGAUUUUCACUUUAGACUGGGUGGUAUGGUGAAAAGAGUAUGAACUUUAAGUCCUGGCCAGUGGCUUCAACCCCUGUGACAUAGGACACAUUUGUAACCUCUGUGAGCUCCAGUUUAAUCUGUAAAACGGGUUUAAAAUACCUAGCUCAUAAGAUGCUAUGAGAUUUUGAGGUGGUGUCUAUAGAUGCCUCGCCCAGUGCUACUCUGGGAGCAGAGUGGAGGGUGGGUUGGCAUAGUUGAGGCUGGAGACUGCUGCAGAGGUCAUUAGGAUGGAUCAGUGGAGGCCAGACUGGGAAGAUUGAGGGCUUGGUCAGUGGGACUUGGUCAUGUAGCAGCAGGCAUGGUGAGUUUUAUGUGUCUCUGAGGUUUCCAACCUGGAUUCCUGGAGUAUCCCAGUGUGGAUUGGAGAAGAGGCAAGUGUGUGGAGAACUGUUGACCAAGUUUCCAUUUUGGACAUGUUGAAUUUGAGAUGCCUGUGGGCCAUUUGAGGGAAGACAAGGAGACAUUAGCAGAGUCUGGGGAGAGGCCAGCCUGGGCUGGAGAUGUGGGCAUUACCAGCAUGUGUGUGAAGCCUGGAUAUGGGUGAGGUUACUCUGAAAGGAGAUAAGAGGAGCAGUCCUAUGUGAAGGGCAGGCCAAAGAAGAGAAGGAGAGAGAAACCAGAAACUGUGAGGAGAGGCACUCAGCUAUAUGGCAUGUACCAGAGAGGCCAAACCACCCUUUGGUACUUCAGAAGUUAUUGCAUCGUGGUUGUAAACUCCAGUUUUUAAUGACCUUAGUUCCCCCCACCCCCUGCCUCCAACAGUCUUAUGAGGAAUUCCAGUUAUAACUGGCUUCUUUGGUGGAAUUUGAGAUACACUCUCUUCUCUGUUAAGCAAAUACUGCAGAUUACAAAUAUUUCAGUUCCAGGUAAGUAGUUAUGUGAUGUGUAAUGGAAACUUUAUAUAUAUUCAUCUUAAUGUUUUAGGGCCACAAUGUGUCAUUUAUUUAAAAAAUAAUAGUGCAAAUGCCACUUAAUAAGGGAAGAGGUCUUUGGGGAUGAAUUUGCCAAACAUUUUUGGAGAAGAUAGCUAUUUGUUUAUUUAUUUAUUUAUUUAUUUUAGGGAAGGGGAAGAAGGUCACUGGUUGGAUUUUAAGUACCUUUUCACAGUCAUUUGUGAUACUACUGGGUUCUAGGGGUCUGGAGAAAGGAUGCUGUCCUGUAAUGAUAGCACCAGUGCUGGAAGCUGCAGCUCCUGGAACUAAGGGAGGUAUAUUUAGUCUUUGAAGGAGUUCCACCCUUCCAGGUGGUGUCUGUAGAUUAGCCAGUGUAUAUGACGGUUCAUGGGUUGAAGGAGAAGCAGCAAAGCCAGGGGAGGCUACUGGUCUGUAGGACUGUGUGAUCUGCUUAGGGCCCAGUGAGAUGGUAAGGGGAAAGUUUUAAAUGAAGGAAAUACUAGGUUCUACAGGAAGUGGCACUUACAUUUUACACAGUGGUUGAGCUUAAGGUUUCAUUUGCUUUGGCUUGGUCCUAUAAAUACCUAUAGGUCUUAGAGCGAAGGGAGUCUGCACAUCAUCAGUUCAAAGUGAAAGCACUGCAUUCAAUUGACUUUGCUUUUGCAAAGAUAGGGAGAUGACCAGUAACUUUUUGAGUCAGAACAAAUAGGGAAGAGUGGUCAGUGGCAUGGAAAUAGUUUUGCUCCCACUGAGCAAUAUGUCUAUCAGCAAUACGAAGACCAGAGAUACCUCUUGCAGCAUCCAAUGUCCUCAAUAACAUUGCAGUAUUUUUAAUUUCUGGCUAUACUUUUUCCUUCUCCGAGGUAUGAAGAAAACAUGAGGCACCACCAGUUACAUCCGGUGAUCAAGGCUUUCCUGUGUGGCUCCAUCAGUGGGACCUGCUCUACCCUCCUUUUCCAACCUCUGGAUCUCCUUAAAACACGCCUGCAAACCCUCCAGCCCUCAGAUCAUGGGUCUAGACGUGUUGGGAUGUUGGCUGUACUCUUGAAGGUGGUUCGCACGGAGAGUCUUUUGGGCCUUUGGAAAGGGAUGUCCCCUUCCAUUGUGAGAUGUGUCCCUGGCGUUGGAAUCUACUUUGGCACUCUCUACUCUUUGAAGCAGUAUUUCUUGCGAGGCCAUCCCCCAACCGCCCUGGAGUCAGUCAUGCUGGGGGUGGGCUCUCGCUCUGUUGCAGGGGUCUGUAUGUCACCUAUCACUGUAAUCAAGACGCGCUAUGAGAGUGGGAAAUAUGGCUAUGAGAGUAUCUACGCUGCCCUGAGGAGCAUCUAUCACAGUGAGGGGCACCGGGGCCUCUUCAGUGGCCUGACAGCAACUCUCCUUCGAGAUGCGCCCUUCUCAGGAAUCUACCUGAUGUUUUACAACCAGACCAAAAAUAUAGUGCCUCAUGACCAGGUGGAUGCAACCCUUAUUCCUAUUACAAAUUUCAGCUGUGGGAUAUUUGCUGGUAUUCUGGCCUCACUGGUAACUCAACCUGCGGAUGUUAUCAAAACUCAUAUGCAGCUUUAUCCACUGAAGUUUCAAUGGAUUGGCCAAGCAGUGACACUUAUUUUCAAAGACUAUGGACUACGUGGCUUCUUCCAAGGUGGCAUCCCCCGAGCCCUCCGCAGAACUCUAAUGGCAGCAAUGGCGUGGACGGUGUAUGAAGAGAUGAUGGCCAAGAUGGGCCUGAAGUCCUGACCAAGAGAGGACUGGGAACGGGUGAAAUCUGUUGCCCUGCUUGGUUUCUGCCAAGGGCUGCUGCUUCUUACUAUUCUGCAGUAAGAUGAAGUCCUACCUGGAAAACCAGGCAGAAAUUGUGUUGCCUUUGCCUUCAGUAAUCCCCUUAAGGAGAAAAUAUAUGGACCUGAUUUCAGCCUUCAGAAUCUCCAAAAGAGGAGUCAUCAAUUCAUAGAGCACACUAGGGUGUUAGGAGAGAGCUUUGCAUACUCUGAGAGGCUACUUGGAAAGGCAUUUUCCCAGGAGAGCUCUGUCAGGUGGCUGCGCUUCAGCCCCACCCCUACACCACAGGGUCUCCUUGGGUAUGUUCUUGGGCAAGCAAUCACAAAGCCAGAGAAGCUGUAAGCUGCCUGCCGGGCCUGAGGAGCUCCAACCAGGGAAGACUGGAUGUGAGGAGAGGAGUCACUGUCACCAGGUCACAGACUGACUGAGGUGAUGGUAGGAUGAGGAGGAACAGAUGCCCUUCUUUAAUUGGUUCUCAGUUAACUUCUCAGAGGCUCUGGAGAACGGGACAGUGGCUUUCUAGCCUCUGAAUGUUCCAAAUAAAAUUUUUUGGUCUUGGCCCCUGUACUGUUUUACCUCUAAAUUCUGGCAUUUUUUUUUCCCUGCAAUUAAAGUGCUGUACUUUAUUUAUUGAACUUUAUCAUUGAAAGCUGUUUGGAAAACCUAAAAGAUGUUGUCACACUUCUGUUUUCUUUACCUGUGCCUUAUAAAAAUGGACCAAACCCUUUUCUAAAAUAAAAUAGUUCUAGGGUGGCUGGUUAUUGACCUAUGUAGGUCCCUAAAACCUAA